GAUUUUUUAAUAUAUUUUAGACCUAUGUAUGCUAGUUAUUAAUGUUUAGCCUGAUUAUAAGUAACUUCUGAAUUUGAAAGAAAUUGAGACAUGUAUUUUGAAUCAUAAUAUCCUUGUGUAAGAUUUGUUGUAUGUGAAGAAAAAUCUAGAUUUUUGUAUAUUGUUUUGCUAAAGUAUAUUUCAGUGUGUGCAGGCAAAGUCAUAUUUUUUCUGAAAUAAGAUGGUUAACUGCUUAAUGUUGCAUUAUCAAGAUUAUUUUAUAUCAUCACAGAAUUGUAUUCAAACCUGUUCAUAAUACUGUGCUUCAGUUUUCAGAACUUCCUCCUACAGGGAUAAUCAUCCCUCAAUAUCCAUGAGAGGGUAGUUCCAGGACCCCACCAAGGAUACCAAAAUCCACAGAUGCUGAAAUUUCUUAUAUAAAAUUGAAUAGUCUAUGCAUCAAUAAAUCCUCUGUAUGCUUUAAAUUAGUGGUCCCCAACCUUUUCAGCACCAGGAACCAGUUUUAUGGAAGACAAUUUUUCCAUGGACCAAGGUUCAGUGGGCUUGGUUUUGGGAUGAAACUGUUCCACCUCAGAUCAUCAGGCAUUAGAUUCUCAUGAGGAGUGUGCAACCUAGGUCCCUUGCGUGUGCAGUUCACAAUAGGGCUCUUGCUCCUGUGAGAAUCUAAUGCUGCUGCUGAUCUGACAGGAGGCGGAGCUCAGGAGGUCAUGCUCGCUUGCCCUCCCCUCCCCUCCUGCUGUGCAGCGCCAUUCUUGAAAGGCCCGGGGUUAGGGACCUCUGCUUUAAAUCAUCUCUAGUUGAUUUAUAGUACUUAAUACAAUGCAAAUGCUAUCUAAAUAGUUAUACUGUCUUUUUUUAUUUUUGUUUUAUUCUUAUUUUUAUUUUUUUUCUGAAUAUUUUCUCUCAAUGCUUGGUUGAAUCCCCAUCUAUGGAACCCGUGGAUACAGAGGGCCAGCUGUAGUUAUAUUACACAUAAUUAUUGGAUAUAAUUCAUACAGUUAAAAAAUUUAAGAGGGAAAAGUGAAUAGAAGUAAAAGCAUUACAAAAGAAGAAGUUUAGAUCAGUGUACGAAGAAGCUAUAAGAAAAACAUCAAAGGUCCAACGUGGAGAUUGUCAGGGCUGCUGGCGGUGUGGAGAGUGACUGAAGGUGCAAGCUGCAUGUCGGGGGAGCUGGCGGUGUGCAGAGUGACUGAAGGUGCAAGCUGCAUGUCGGAGCUGGCGGUGUGGAGAGUGACUGAAGGUGCAAGCUGCAUGUCGGGGGAGCCGGCGGUGUGCAGAGUGACUGAAGGUGCAGGCUGCAUGUCGGAGCUGGCGGUGUGCAGAGUGACUGAAGGUGCAAGCUGCAUGUCGGGGGAGCUGGCAGUGUGGAGAGUGACUGAAGGUGCAAGCUGCAUGUCGGGGGAGCUGGCGGUGUGCAGAGUGACUGAAGGUCCAGGCUGCAUGUCGGGGUUGCUGGCGGUGUGCAGAGUGACUGAAGGUGCAGGCUGCAUGUCGGGGGAGCUGGCGGUGUGCAGAGUGACUGAAGGUGCAAGCUGCAUGUCGGGGGAGCUGGCGGUGUGCAGAGUGACUGAAGGUGCAGGCUGCAUGUCGGGGCUGCUGGCGGUGUGCAGAGUGACUGAAGGUGCAGGCUGCAUGUCGGGGGAGCUGGCGGUGUGCAGAGUGACUGAAGGUGCAAGCUGCAUGUCAGGGGAGCUGCCGGUGUGGAGAGUGACUGAAGGUGCAGGCUGCAUGUCGGGGGAGCUGGCGGUGUGCAGAGUGACUGAAGGUGCAGGCUGCAUGUCGGGGGAGCUGGCGGUGUGCAGAGUGACUGAAGGUGCAGGCUGCAUGUCGGGGGAGCUGGCGGUGUGCAGAGUGACUGAAGGUGCAGGCUGCAUGUCGGGGGAGCUGACGGUGUGCAGAGUGACUGAAGGUGCAGGCUGCAUGUCGGGGGAGCUGGCGGUGUGGAGAGUGACUGAAGGUGCAGGCUGCAUGUCGGGGGAGCUGGCGGUGUGCAGAGUGACUGAAGGUGCAGGCUGCAUGUCGGGGGAGCUGGCGGUGUGGAGAGUGACUGAAGGUGCAGGCUGCAUGUCGGGGGAGCUGGCGGUGUGCAGAGUGACUGAAGGUGCAAGCUGCAUGUCAGGGGAGCUGCCGGUGUGGAGAGUGACUGAAGGUGCAAGCUGCAUGUCGGGGGAGCUGGCGGUGUGCAGAGUGACUGAAGGUGCGGGCUGCAUGUCGGGGGAGCUGGCAGUGUGCAGAGUGACUGAAGGUGCGGGCUGCAUGUCGGGGGAGCUGGCGGUGUGCAGAGUGACUGAAGGUGCGGGCUGCAUGUCGGGGGAGCUGGCGGUGUGCAGAGUGACUGAAGGUGCGGGCUGCAUGUCGGGGGAGCUGGCGGUGUGCAGAGUGACUGAAGGUGCGGGCUGCAUGUCGGGGGAGCUGGCGGUGUGCACAGUGACUGAAGGUGCAAGCUGCAUGUCGGGGGAGCUGGCGGUGUGCAGAGUGACUGAAGGUGCACGCUGCAUGUCGGGGGAGCCGGCGGUGUGGAGAGUGACUGAAGGUGCAGGCUGCAUGUCGGGGGAGCUGGCGGUGUGGAGAGUGACCGAAGGUGCAGGCUGCAUGUCGGGGGAGCUGGCGGUGUGGAGAGUGACUGAAGGUGCAGGCUGCAUGUCGGGGGAGCUGGCGGUGUGCACAGUGACUGAAGGUGCAAGCUGCAUGUCGGGGGAGCUGGCGGUGUGCAGAGUGACUGAAGGUCCAUGCUGCGUGUCGGGGGAGCUGGCGGUGUGCAGAGUGACUGAAGGUCCAUGCUGCAUAUCGGGGGAGUGCAUUCGGAGUGUUCUCAUCUGUCUCAUCCCUGACCACGUGAGUACGCAGGACACCUGUGUCUGUGUUAAGGGAGUUCGUUCCUAAGUGCUCUCAUCUGCCUACUUCCAUGACUGUGUGAGUAAAAAGGGCUCAGGUCACACACAAGAAGGAAGAAAUUGGAAACCCAGGAACACAUAUCAGAGGAAACCAACUGAAAACAAAUAAUAAAAUGCAGACGUACGUUCUAAUGGUCUAAAUACGAGACAGAAUGGAUAAAAAACAAAAAAACCAAGACGCAUUUCUAUGUUGUGUGCACGAAAGUCUCUUCAAAUACAGUGACAUAGAUAGGAUGAAAGUAAAAGGAUAGAAAAAUAGAUACAAUGUAAAAUUAAACAAAAGUAGUAGGAGCUAUGUUAAUGUCCAAGAAAGUGUACUUCAGAGUGAAGAAAAUUAACACAGACAAAAAGAGAUGUUAUACAACAAUAAUAGGAUUAAUCCAUCAGGAAGAUACAAUGAUCAUAAAUUGUUACUCACCAAACAACAGUUCCAUAAAAUUCGUGAAUCAACAAGUGUCAGAGCUGAAAAAAGUAGGCAAGUCCAGUUACAAGUGGUUACUUCAGCACCACCCUUCAGGCAUUGGAUAAAAGUAGGGGAUAGACGCUCCGCAGUGAUGUGGAAGAUUUGCAUAGGCAGCAGGAGUUGCCUAGCAUGCAUAGACCACCGUACCUGUCAGUAGGAGAGAACACAUUUAUUUCAAGUGUCUAUAGAACAUUCACCAAGAUAAGCCAUUUUCUGUACCAUAAACCUCAACAAAUUGAAAAGAAUUGAAAUCACACAGAGUGUGUUCUCUCACUGUAAUAGAAUUGUUAAAAAUCAGUAACCAAGGCAGCAGGAAAACUCUAAAACGUGGAAAGUGAACAGCACACUUUGAAUUAAUUUAUAGGAUAGGUAGUCUCAAGGAAACAAUACAUACAGCUGAAUAAAAGUGAAAAUUCUGCAUUCUGGAAUAAGUGGGAUGCGUGUAAGGGCACUGCUGGGAGGAAUUCUGUAGCAUGAAACUCCUGUGGGGAAACAAGCAGAGGUCUUGGGUCAGUAAUCUAAACCCCUACUGCAAGAAAUUAGGAGAAGACAGCAAAGUUAAACCAAGGCAAGCAGAAGGAAGGGAAUAAUAAAGAUACAAGUAGAAGUCAGUAAAAUGGAAAA